AUACCAGUUGUGCUUUUAUACUGGUAGGAUGUGAUUUGGGGAACUAUUAGUUAAACCAAUGAGCUACAAGAAAUGAACCUAGUAAAACUAAGUUGAAUGCUUUAGAGAGACUUGAUUAAGGUGAGUUGUUACCCCUCCCAACUCAAAAUGCUGCUGAAUGAGAAGUGAACAAGACAACUGUAAAAGAUUUGGGAGGCCGGACGCGAUGGUUCACGCCUAUAAUCCCAGCACCGGGAGGCUGAGAGGGUCACCAUGAAGUUCAAUCCCUUCGUUACCUCGGACCGCAGUAAAAACCGCAAACGUCACUUCAAUGCCCCCUCACACGUGCGCAGGAAGAUCAUGUCAUCCCCGCUCUCCAAGGAGCUGCGGCAGAAGUACAAUGUCCGCUCCAUGCCCAUCCGCAAGGACGACGAGGUCCAGGUAGUUCGAGGACACUACAAAGGUCAGCAAAUUGGCAAGGUAGUCCAGGUGUACAGAAAGAAAUAUGUCAUCUACAUCGAGCGGGUGCAGCGUGAGAAGGCCAACGGCACAACUGUCCACGUGGGCAUUCACCCAAGCAAGGUGGUUAUCACCAGGCUAAAACUGGACAAGGAUCGGAAAAAAAUUCUUGAACGCAAAGCCAAGUCUCGACAAGUUGGAAAAGAGAAAGGCAAAUAUAAAGAAGAACUUAUUGAGAAAAUGCAGGAAUAAAUAGAACCUGUUGUGCAACCACGGUUUAACCGGAGAUUUUGAGGCUAGGGUGUGUUUCUUUCGAACUUUUCGGAAUGUCUGGAACAUUUCAUUUCCUGUUUUGUUACCUGUGCCUCUGUAAAUCUACUUUUGCAAUUUUAAGUAAUAAUUUUAUGAAUAAAAAUGGGAAAUGCUUCCUAAUUCCACAUAGUAUUUGCAUUGUUUUAUAAAUAAAUUCCACUUACUAUCAA